CUCUCGUCUCCUCCCCACUGCGCCUCCCUCCCUCCUGGCCUUCCUUCCCUUCCCCGACUUUGCAGAUUUCUCUUCCCCCAGGCCUCCCUCCUCCACCUCUCCGCCCCCUCCGGGCUUGGCUCUCCCAGGAGGCUACGACUGGAGCCACUGGUCCCGCAGGAUCCCCGCGUCCUCGGUCGCCGCGUCCACGUCCCUCUCGCGUCCCCGCCCGGCGCCACGCCGCCUCCUCUGGGUUCGGCCUCCGCGCGGUGCAGCGCAGUCUCAGGCCGCGGGACAAGGUACGUGCGCGUCCCCGGGGCACACAAGCCCACACAAGCCCGGGCCCCGCUCCUCUGAACUCCCGCGUGUGUUCUGACUAUGGCAAAGAAGGUCUUUGCCGCGUGCACGGCCCGACUUAAAUCUCUGCAAUGGCUAACGAAGCUUAUCCUUGUCCGUGUGACAUUGGCCACAGACUUGAGUAUGGAGGGCUAGGCCGUGAAGUUCAAGUCGAGCACAUCAAGGCUUAUGUCACCAAAUCCCCCGUUGAUGCAGGCAAAGCUGUGAUUGUCAUUCAAGAUAUAUUUGGCUGGCAGUUGCCCAAUACCAGAUAUAUAGCUGACAUGAUCUCAGGAAAUGGAUACACAACCAUUGUUCCAGACUUCUUUGUAGGGCAAGAGCCUUGGGACCCCUCUGGCGACUGGUCUAUCUUCCCUGAGUGGCUGAAAACAAGAAAUGCCCAGAAGAUCGAUAGAGAGAUCAGUGCUAUCUUGAAGUAUCUGAAACAACAGUGUCAUGCCCAGAAAAUUGGCAUCGUGGGAUUCUGCUGGGGUGGAACUGCUGUCCAUCAUUUGAUGAUGAAAUACUCAGAAUUCAGGGCAGGGGUGUCCGUCUAUGGCAUUGUCAAGGAUUCUGAAGACAUUUACAAUUUAAAGAACCCCACUUUGUUCAUUUUUGCUGAAAAUGAUGUUGUGAUUCCACUCAAGGACGUAUCUUUGCUGACUCAGAAGUUGAAAGAACACUGCAAAGUUGAAUAUCAAAUUAAAACAUUUUCUGGGCAGACUCAUGGGUUCGUGCAUCGGAAGAGAGAAGAUUGCUCACCUGCAGACAAGCCCUACAUUGACGAGGCCAGAAGGAAUUUAAUUGAGUGGCUGAACAAGUACAUGUAGCAAGAAUCAAGGGCAAGCCUUCCUAGAAUAGCUUUCAUCCCAAAAUUUGCUUGGAAAUAGUUAGAUCAUUUGAUUUAAUUUUCACUUUUAUAAAAUAAGUGUAGGAAUCCUAAAAUUGAUUAUUUCAUUUGAAACACAAAUUCAGUAGGACGUAAUGCAUGAAAUAAUUUAAUUUUUGACAUGUACAUCGAAUCAUAAUUUAAAAACAAGGUCUGACCAGGUGUAGUGCCUCAUGCCUGUAAUUCCAGCACUUUGGGAGGCCAAAGUGGGUGGAUCACCUGAGGUCAGGAGUUUGAGACCAGCCUGGCCAACAUGGUGAGACCCCAUCUCUACAAAAAAUACAAAAAUUAGCCUGGUGUGGUGGUGCACGCCUGUAGUCCCAGCUACUUGGGAGGCUGAGGCACAAGAAUCAAUAGAACCCAGGAGGUGGAGACUGCAGUGAGCCAAGAUUGUGCCACUACUGUACUCUAGCCUGGGCAGCAGAGUGAGACCCUGUCUCAAAAAUAAAUAAGUAAAUAAAUAAAUAAAUAAAAUAAAAACCAGGUCAGUACCUGGAGAAUUUGAAUGAUAGAGAAUGAUAGAGUAAUACCCUAAUUAUUAGUUAAAACCUACAGGCCGGGUGCGGUGGCUCACGCCUGUAAUCCCAGCACUUUGGGAGGCCGAGGUGGGUGGAUCACUUGAGGUCAGGAGUUCAAGACCAGCCUGGCCAACAUGGUGAAACCCCAUCUCUACUAAAAAUAUAAAAAUCAGCCGGGCAUGGUGGCAUGUGCCUGUAAUCCCAGCUACUCAGGAGUCUGAGGAGGAGAAUCACUUGAACCUGGAGGCAGAGGUUGCAGUGAGUCGAGGUUGCGCUACUGCACUCCAGCCUGGACAACAGAGGGAGACUCUGUCUCAAAAAAAAAAAAAAACCUACAGCUGUUCAAGGACCAGCUGACAGGUCAAGUGUGGCCUUUUCUGGUCUUUGAACACAUCAUAGAAAGUGACAAAUGCUGCAAAGCCAUGAAGAACAUGAACUAUAAACGGGUAGACUAACUGCCCAGCUUAGACACUUAUCUAUGCCACAAAACAGCUGAAUUUGUCACAUUUAUAUAUUGCAAUAUGGGAAGUAUUGAGAUCAAAACAGGAUUCCAUUGACCUAAUUAUAUUAAGCUAAUAAACUAAUUUUUUGAAUUUUUGAAUUUGCAGCUUUUUUAAAAAGAUAGCAGAGAACGGUGGGCUAGAGUUGUCACCCAGCUGUUGUCUCCUAAGCAGUGGAUUUCCAAGCACUGGCAUUUUUGGGUCCCAGGGCCUGAGGCUACCUCAGAAAUAUCUCCUGUGUUUCUGGUGGUGGCGUAAAGGGGAGAGCCGGUGAGAAACUCUGCACCUGCACCUACGGGGUGCGUACAUGUGACUUUGGGCAAGUGACUUGAUGUUGUAGUUUUUUUCCUAAUUUUGUCUUGACGUCCUUCUCAGGAGAGAGUGGCUGUAAACUCUAGCCCUGCCCUGACGGGGAUCCUGGGGAUGUGGUCGUGGGUGUUUCCCAUGUGCCUUUCAUGGGAUCCUUCUUUGACCUCACAGACGGCCUGAUUCCUGAGUGUCCAACCUGUGGCCAGGUGUCCCUCUCGCAGGAAGCUUGUUUAUCCUGGCACAUGACCUUGUGGCUCUCAUCUGACCUGUGUCCAGUUUAUUCCUACUGAGACAGCCACUCUCCCGGAGAGCCCUGACCGGGAAAGAAGUUAGGAUGGGGUAGAGGAGGCAACUCAUCAGAACCCAAGAAAUGACAGAAGCAGUUUAUUGCUUACAGAUCCAGAGAACAGAGGGCAGCACGCUUCACAGGGCCAGCAAAAAGGGGGAGCCAUUCAGGACACAUGGGCUCAACCAGAAGGUGGAGAACGAGAGAGAGAGGGAGCUAUGAGCCAAAGCCUUCACUGGGGCCCAGGGUGUCAUCUAUGCAGGUUUCCCCUGGAGGUUCUAACUGGGGGGUUUAGAGCAAGCAGGCAUGAGCCCCGGGGACUCACGCUGUGACUGAGAGGGGUCGGUGUGGGUAGGAUAUCGGCAUGGUCCAUGUGGGUGUGGGGGUCAGUGGGACAAGUCAAGCAGGUGGUAUCCAGCUGUCCAUGGGAAGGUGGUCCCAGGAGGCGGUUUUGUAAGGCAGAUGUCUGGAUCGACCACCUUGGGGAACAGUGAGAAGUUGUAUAACUGGAAACUGUGUUACUAAUCCCUGCUUCUAGUAUGAGAAAGUCCAACUUACAUUCAAAUAGAUGCUCAGGAAACAUAAAAUUCAAAGAAUUCCCAAACUUGAGCUUCCUGAGCCUCAGUUUUUGCAUCUGUCAAAUGGGUAUGGGGAGACCCUUUGCCUAAUGUUGAGAGAAUCCAAGCCUGAGCAGGGCUGGUCUACUGUGGACACUUAGUUGUGGACCCCAACAGGCCAAAGCCCUUGCCUGCUGAGGGCUGCUCCCAGGAGGCCUCACACAUUCAUCCGGCCUCCCAGGAAACCCCUGAGAUGUGCUGGGCUUUUGCCGUGGAACGGUGUCGGUGAGCAUGUGGCCAGUAGCCAGAGUCUUCAACAUAGGUGGGAGGUCUGAAAUUCGUGCGAGAAUGAACCAAGGGUGUGGCUGUAUCCUUCAUGGUGAGCUUGGGGCCUGGGCAGCCUUCCCUCUGCUGAGUCCUUUGGUCAAAUGUCAUGGUGUUCUGAACCAGCACUGCAGAUAGAAGUAUAAUGUAAGUCACACACGUACUUCUUUAAAAAGAUAUGUUCUUCAGUGACUAUUAGACAAACAGAUAAAUGAAGGUAAAGGGAAAAAAUGGCAACUUUAGCUUUUUUCCCCAUGUAUGUAAUUUUAAAUUUUCUUAUAGCCCCAUUAAAAAAAGGAAAGAGA